GCACUCCAGCACUGCGCAGGGACCGGUGAGUGUCGCUUCUGGGGGCAGCGCCCAGUAACCGCGCUAGGAGCGCGGAGAAGGGCAUUGGGAGAGCGGCGUUCGUGGCGGAGACUAGCGCUCCGGAGCACGGGCACGACGGGGGCACCUUCUCGGCUGCUACCUUGGACCGCAGUUGCCGGCCAGGAAUCCCAGUGUCACGGUGGACACGCCUCCCUCGCGCCCUUGCCGCCCACCUGCUCACCCAGCUCAGGGGCUUUGGAAUUCUGUGGCCACACUGCGAGGAGAUCGGUUCUGGGUCGGAGGCUACAGGAAGACUCCCACUCCCUGAAAUCUGGAGUGAAGAACGCCGCCAUCCAGCCACCAUUCCAAGGAGGUGCAGGAGAACAGCUCUGUGAUACCAUUUAACUUGUUGACAUUACUUUUAUUUGAAGGAACGUAUAUUAGAGCUUACUUUGCAAAGAAGGAAGAUGGUUGUUUCCGAAGUGGACAUCGCAAAAGCUGAUCCAGCUGCUGCAUCCCACCCUCUAUUACUGAAUGGAGAUGCUACUGUGGCCCAGAAAAAUCCAGGCUCGGUGGCUGAGAACAACCUGUGCAGCCAGUAUGAGGAGAAGGUGCGCCCCUGCAUCGACCUCAUUGACUCCCUGCGGGCUCUAGGUGUGGAGCAGGACCUGGCCCUGCCAGCCAUCGCCGUCAUCGGGGACCAGAGCUCGGGCAAGAGCUCCGUGUUGGAGGCACUGUCAGGAGUUGCCCUUCCCAGAGGCAGCGGGAUCGUGACCAGAUGCCCGCUGGUGCUGAAACUGAAGAAACUUGUGAACGAAGAUAAGUGGAGAGGCAAGGUCAGUUACCAGGACUACGAGAUUGAGAUUUCGGAUGCUUCAGAGGUAGAAAAGGAAAUUAAUAAAGCCCAGAAUGCCAUCGCCGGGGAAGGAAUGGGAAUCAGUCAUGAGCUAAUCACCCUGGAGAUCAGCUCCCGAGAUGUCCCGGAUCUGACUCUAAUAGACCUUCCUGGCAUAACCAGAGUGGCUGUGGGCAAUCAGCCUGCUGACAUUGGGUAUAAGAUCAAGACACUCAUCAAGAAGUACAUCCAGAGGCAGGAGACAAUCAGCCUGGUGGUGGUCCCCAGUAAUGUGGACAUCGCCACCACAGAGGCUCUCAGCAUGGCCCAGGAGGUGGACCCCGAGGGAGACAGGACCAUCGGAAUCUUGACGAAGCCUGAUCUGGUGGACAAAGGAACUGAAGACAAGGUUGUGGACGUGGUGCGGAACCUCGUGUUCCACCUGAAGAAGGGUUACAUGAUUGUCAAGUGCCGGGGCCAGCAGGAGAUCCAGGACCAGCUGAGCCUGUCCGAAGCCCUGCAGAGAGAGAAGAUCUUCUUUGAGAACCACCCAUAUUUCAGGGAUCUGCUGGAGGAAGGAAAGGCCACGGUUCCCUGCCUGGCAGAAAAACUUACCAGCGAGCUCAUCACACAUAUCUGUAAAUCUCUGCCCCUGUUAGAAAAUCAAAUCAAGGAGACUCACCAGAGAAUAACAGAGGAGCUACAAAAGUAUGGUGUCGACAUACCGGAAGACGAAAAUGAAAAAAUGUUCUUCCUGAUAGAUAAAGUUAAUGCCUUUAAUCAGGACAUCACUGCUCUCAUGCAAGGAGAGGAAACUGUAGGGGAGGAAGACAUUCGGCUGUUUACCAGACUCCGACACGAGUUCCACAAAUGGAGUACAAUAAUUGAAAACAAUUUUCAAGAAGUUCUGGAGGCUGGAAGUCCAAGAUCAAGAUGUUGGUGGAGCUGGUUCCUUCUAAGGCCUCUCUCCUUGCCUUGCAGAUGGCCUCUUCUCAUUGGGUCCUCAUGUGGUUGUCCCUCAGUGUGUGUGUCCUCAUCUCCUCCCACAAGGACACUAGGCAGAUGGGAUGAGGGCCCACCCUAGUGACCUGAUUUCAAUUUAAUUACCUCUUUGCCUGUCUCCAAACACAGUCAGAUUCUGAGUUUCUGAGGGUUAGGACUUCAACAUUGGAGUUUGAAGAGGUCACAACUCAAGCUCAGCCCGUAACACCAAGUCCUGGAAUAUUUCCAGCCACAGACAGGCACAGAGUGCUGGUCCACAGCACCCCAUGGAUGAACCUUGAAAAUGUCAUGCUGAGUGAAAGAAGCCAGCCACAAAGGCCACACGGUCUAUGAUUCCAUUGAUAGAAAAUGGCUAGAACAGGCAAACCCAGGCAGGCAGAAAGCAGAAUAGUGGCUGCCAGGGGCUGGGGAGGGAAAAGUGGGAAGUUAUCACUGAUGGGUGAUGGAUGUGGGGUUUGGGAGUUAUGUCUGGGGAUGGUCGCACAACUUUGUGAAUAUACUAAAAUUCACUCACCCAUACACUUUUUUUUUUCUUUUUCUUUGGAGACAGGGUCUCACUCUGUUGCCCAGGCUGGGGUGCAGUGGCUCAGUCUCGGCUCACUGCACCCUCUGCCUCCCAGAUUCAAGCGAUUCUCCUGCUUCAGCCUCCACCUCCCUAGUAGCUGGGAUUAUAGGCACCUGUCUAAUUUUUGUAUUUUUAGUAGAGAUGGGGUUUCACCAUGUUGGCCAGGCUGGUCUCGACCUCCUGACCUCAGGUGAUCACUGGCCUCAGCCUCCCAGAGUGUUGGGAUUACGGGCGUGAGCCACUGUGCCUGGCCUGAACCAUAUAUUUUUAACAGAGUGAAUGUUAUACUAUGUAAAUGACAUCUCAAUUAGAAAAAUCCUUAUGGGAAAAUAUUUCCUGACUAAAAAAAGUGUUCUAGAUUACCACUCAAAAAGGAACUCAAACCCUCUGAACUUCUGAUGGGGCUAACUCUCUCUAGUGUGGAUUGUUGGGAGUACAAAUCAUUCCAAAAGUUUAAAGAAAAAUGCAGCAUCUUACACAGUGAACAGUGCUACUGUAUCACAUUCAUACAAGUUGAUGUGCCUGGUUUACUCUGUUAUCCCAUUUGACUUGUAAACACUUUCUACACAUGGCAAUACUUUCGACACAUGAAUAUGUGAUGUAUUGUUAAUUCCAGAAAGUGUUCAUGCUCAUUUCUAAUGGGCAUGCAGUUGAGGGCAAGGAGUGUAUUAUGGUACAAUUUCUUUGGUAAAACUAAAAUUGGAUUCACAAAACUUCAUACUCGAGUACGUUUUUAAGAAGGGGUCUUGGCCGGGCACGGUGGCUCACGCCUGUAAUCCCAGCACUUUGGGAGGCCGAGGCAGGUGGAUCAUGAGGUCAGGAAAUUGAGACCAUCCUGGCUAACACGGUGAAACCCCGUCUCUACUAAAAAUACAAAAAAAUUAGCCGGGCGUGGUGGCGGGUACCUGUAGUCCCAGCUACUUGGGAGGCUGAGGCAGAAGAAUGGCGUGAACCCGGGAGGCAGAGCUUGCAGUGAGCUGAGAUCACGCCACUGCACUCCAGCCUGGGUGACAGAGCGAGACUCUGUCACAAACAAACAAAUGAAAAAAAAGGGUCUUACUCGAAGUUUCUGCGUAUGUGGGUUCCUGGCAUCGUACCUGGCUCUGCACUCCCCUUCCUGAGAUGACUAAGGAAAAUUAUCUUCAGAUCUGGUUUUGUGUGUGUGUGUGUGUGUGUGUGUGUGUGUGUGUGUGUGUGUGUGUGUAAUCCCUGGAUAUUUUUAGUUUACCAGUUAGAUUUGAUUUGAUACCACUUUUUCUUGCCAUUUAUAUUUUCAGAAAAUUUAGAAUGGUAUUGUGUUUAGAAAAAUGUGCAAGAUUAUUUUUGUAAAAUAAUUUAGAGGGUUUUUUUUCCUGCUAUAGGCCAUAAAAUUUUGAGUAGAAAAA